AGUCUUGCACGCCUCCAGGGCUGGAAAGCUCAUUCUUCUUCUUCCUCCCAGCAGCUCUGCCUGGAAGUCCCCCAAUCCCUGUGCUCCUGCCCCCAGAUCGUGGGCUUGGGGGACAGCAAGAAAGCUGCAAAGGACUCAGCUGGGGCGGCUCCACAAGGACCCCACAGGCUUGAGGUGUUGCCAGGAUUCUAUCCCAGGGGGUUUUCUGGGUCCCCCAGAGCCCUCUCAAGCACGGGGAGGCAGAAGGGUCCUCGCCCAUUUCAGGAAUCUGCAGCCUGGAAGCCACAGCCAUGGCAGGCCCCCGAUACCCAGUUUCAGUGCAAGGGGCAGCCCUGGUGCAGAUCAAGAGGCUCCAAACGUUUGCCUUCUCUGUGCGCUGGUCAGACGGCAGCGACACCUUCGUGCGCAGGAGUUGGGACGAAUUCAGGCAGCUCAAGAAGACCCUCAAGGAGACCUUCCCGGUGGAGGCGGGCCUGCUGCGGAGAUCUGACCGCGUUCUCCCAAAGCUUCUCGGUCAGGCCAGCCUGGAUGCACCACUGUUGGGACGCGUGGGGCGCACGAGCCGCGGCCUGGCGCGCCUGCAGCUGUUGGAAACCUAUUCUCGGAGGCUGCUGGCGACUGCAGAGCGCGUGGCACGGAGCCCGACGAUCACUGGCUUCUUCGCACCGCAACCCCUGGACCUGGAGCCCGCGCUGCCACCCGGCAGCCGGGUGAUCCUGCCCACCCCAGAGGAGCAGCCUCUUUCUCGCGCUGCGGGCCGCCUCUCCAUCCACAGUCUGGAGGCUCAGAGCCUGCGCUGCCUGCAGCCCUUCUGUACCCAGGACACGCGGGAUAGGCCUUUUCAGGCGCAGGCCCAGGAGAGCCUGGACGUGCUGCUGCGGCACCCCUCAGGCUGGUGGCUGGUGGAGAACGAAGACCGGCAGACCGCCUGGUUUCCAGCGCCCUACCUGGAGGAGGCGGCCCCGGGCCAAGGCCGGGAGGGAGGCCCGUCCCUAGGGAGCAGCGGUCCCCAGUUCUGUGCUUCCCGCGCCUACGAGAGCAGCCGCGCAGAUGAGCUGUCCGUGCCCGCGGGGGCGCGCGUGCGCGUGUUGGAAACGUCAGACCGCGGCUGGUGGCUAUGCAGGUACGGCGACCGGGCGGGCCUACUCCCCGCGGUGCUGCUGCGGCCGGAAGGGCUGGGCGCUCUCCUGAGCGGGACGGGGUUCCGUGGAGGAGACGACCCGGCGGGUGAGGCCCGGGGCUUCCCUGAACCCUCCCAGGCCACCGCCCCUCCCCCCACCGUGCCCACCCGACCUUCGCCGGGCGCCAUCCAGAGCCGCUGCUGCACCGUCACACGCAGGGCCCUGGAGCGGCGCCCACGGCGCCAGGGCCGCCCUCGAGGGUGCGUGGACUCUGUGCCGCACCCCACGACGGAGCAGUGAGCGCGAGGAUCCCGAUGAGGGGAUGGACCGCGCCAUCCCAGGGCUGGGGAGGAGCGGGGAGGGCGGAUCUCCCUGGCCAGCAGGGAUGGGAGGGGGCCAUUUGCUGUUCCUCUGAGUAAAGCUUGUUCUGCAUGA